AUACGGAGGGACUCUUGUGACCAGACUGUCCUGGGGCAGUGCCUGGUGCUCAUGGCUCAAGGCACAGUUCUGCUGGGGCUGGUGCUGCUGCCAUCCAGGUGGUGAGAAAGUAAGCAGACCCAGAGGGGUCCUGAGCGGGGAGCGGGGUCAGUGUCUGAGCCUCUCCUUCUCUCCCCAGGGGCUUUGGCUUAGGAUCCAGGAGAUGGCCUUAGAGUGCAGGAGCUGGUGACGGUGCAGGAGGGAAUGUGCAGGCAUGUGCUCUGCGCUGUUUUCUACCCCAAGUAUUACUGGGCAGGAUCCGGCCUAGCUCAUGGUUACUGCCAACAGGAUGAAGCCACUCCUGGAAGGAACACUCCAGUGGCUACAAACAACCCCAAACAAUUGCAGGAGAAGAACCAGGGCCAGUUCACCUCGUUGGUCAUCCCCAGACCUACAGCUGCUCCCUGAACCUCAGAGAUGCCAAUGAGGCGGAUACAGGGACGUACUUCUUUCAGUGCUGACCCAGCCACCUGAGAUCCAUGUCCAGAAGAGCUGCAAUCAGGUGACCCUGGAAAUCUGACUUGCACCGUAUCAUGGGCCGCCCCAAAGACCCUGAACAAUGGUACACCACUGCCUGUCCUGGAGGGAGAGUCCCUGUGGUCUGUGUGGCUGACAGCACCCCACCUCCCAACCCCGCCCGGCUGAGCUGGUCCUGAGAGGGAAGAACACUGAAUUCCUCCCAGCUCUCAGCACCCGGGGGCCUGGAGCUGCCUCAGAUAGGGGCUGGGACGGAGGAGCAUUGACCUGUUGGGCUCACCACCCACUGCGAUUUCAGCACAUUUCCCUGAGCCUCUGUGCAGAGAAGCCCCUCUGGCUACAGAUGUGUGAGUGAAAAGCAGGAGGGCUUCUGGCCCCUGGUUCUCACCUGAUCAGGGGGCCAUCCUGGGCACUGGCUUCCCCCCAACCCCCAUGGCCUCACCUGGAGCUACUACUCCAGGUGUGGAGGGCCCCAGGGGAGCAGUGCUGAGAGGCCUGACUGAGCCCCUCCUGCUCAAGACAGAACUCAGAUGUGGACACCCAGCCCUGCAGAACAGAUGCAGGACAACACUGUCAGCCAUGGCUCAGCCCUUCUGACCAUUGCAGUUGAGAUGCUGCAACUUCCCAGGGAGCGACUGGGCAAACAUGGGGGCCUGAGAAAACUGACAUCGGUCUAAGGAGGCUCCACCACACAGGAUACUCCCAGUUCCUCCCAGCCCAGCCACACAGUUACAAAAAAUCUUCUGCUGAAUUCAGGUGCAUGUUUCUUCUCCCAUGAAAUCCUGCCCAUCGCGGAGGGUGCAUGCCCCGGGGCUGGUGUCCUCACUCCACAUCUCCUGUUCACCGGGACCCCUGGGAGCAGAGCUUGCAGAAGCAAAGCCCCAGGGCCAGCUGAUCCCUCAUGUUCUGGAGUAACCAGGGAAGUGUGGCUGAGCGAGACAUCGGUGGUGAAGAAACCCUUCGUGGUGCAGUGAGGAAAGGAGAAAUAUCUUCCCUUUUGAAAUCUGCCCCUUUUCUUCCGAAUUUCCUCCCUUCCAAGCCCCACAGUACAACAGUCACAGCCUCAGUUUCCCAGACCUCCUGCGAGCCAGGCUCCCCUCUGUGUCCUUGGCGUGUAUCAACACAUAGAAUCCUCACCUCCACAGCCCCAUGUCCCUCUGCUCAGUCCUCCUGAGAUUGAACCCCUGACCUACGGGAGAGUGACCCCAUCCUGCCUGUGCCCCCCAACUGAAGCUCCUGCCGUGGACAGCUCAGACGUCAGGAGCCUCCAUGUCUCCCCUCCGCACAGUGACCCCUUGGGGACAGUGUCCAGCUCUGCUGUGUUGACCUCGUUGUGCAGAAAGGGGGUGCCCACCUCGUGCUUGCUUGGGGGGGAUGAGAGGCUGCCUGCUCACCCCACCUGCACCCCCAUCUCUCAUGGCCCCAAGUCCCACCUCUGAGCUACGCAGAUAUCCACAGCCUCUGACUCAGGGGUCUGGCCAGAUGGGACUCAUUUUCACCCUGCAGAAAAUGUCACCUAAGGGGAAGGGCAUUGAGAGGGAGGCAGGAGGUGGGGUGGGCCCUGCAUGGGGUGGGAAUCUGGGUGAGUCUGUCUCCCGCUCUGGCCUCAGGGACCCAGGAGUGAACAUGGGGUGGUGGACGGUGGAUCUCCCAGGGCUGACCCGGGCCUGACAGUGUCUGGGUGUAAAGUUCCUCCUCUGAGGAGGUCACUGUUCCGACCUCGCCCCUGUCUUCCUGUAGGGCCUCCUCUAAGUCUUGAGCCCGCAGUUCCUGAGAGAAGAACCCUGAGGAACAGACGUUCCCUCGCGGCCCUGGCACCUCUAACCCCAGACAUGCUGCUGCUGCUGCUGCCCCUGCUCUGGGGGAGGGAGAGGGCGGAAGGACAGACAAGUAAACUGCUGACGAUGCAGAGUUCCGUGACGGUGCAGGAAGGCCUGUGUGUCCAUGUGCCCUGCUCCUUCUCCUACCCCUCGCAUGGCUGGAUUUACCCUGGCCCAGUAGUUCAUGGCUACUGGUUCCGGGAAGGGGCCAAUACAGACCAGGAUGCUCCAGUGGCCACAAACAACCCAGCUCGGGCAGUGUGGGAGGAGACUCGGGACCGAUUCCACCUCCUUGGGGACCCACAUACCAAGAAUUGCACCCUGAGCAUCAGAGAUGCCAGAAGAAGUGAUGCGGGGAGAUACUUCUUUCGUAUGGAGAAAGGAAGUAUAAAAUGGAAUUAUAAACAUCACCGGCUCUCUGUGAAUGUGACAGCCUUGACCCACAGGCCCAACAUCCUCAUCCCAGGCACCCUGGAGUCCGGCUGCCCCCAGAAUCUGACCUGCUCUGUGCCCUGGGCCUGUGAGCAGGGGACACCCCCUAUGAUCUCCUGGAUAGGGACCUCCGUGUCCCCCCUGGACCCCUCCACCACCCGCUCCUCGGUGCUCACCCUCAUCCCACAGCCCCAGGACCAUGGCACCAGCCUCACCUGUCAGGUGACCUUCCCUGGGGCCAGCGUGACCACGAACAAGACCGUCCAUCUCAACGUGUCCUACCCGCCUCAGAACUUGACCAUGACUGUCUUCCAAGGAGACGGCACAGUAUCCACAGUCUUGGGAAAUGGCUCAUCUCUGUCACUCCCAGAGGGCCAGUCUCUGCGCCUGGUCUGUGCAGUUGAUGCAGUUGACAGCAAUCCCCCUGCCAGGCUGAGCCUGAGCUGGAGAGGCCUGACCCUGUGCCCCUCACAGCCCUCAAACCCGGGGGUGCUGGAGCUGCCUUGGGUGCACCUGAGGGAUGCAGCUGAAUUCACCUGCAGAGCUCAGAACCCUCUCGGCUCUCAGCAGGUCUACCUGAACGUCUCCCUGCAGAGCAAAGCCACAUCAGGAGUGACUCAGGGGGUGGUCGGGGGAGCUGGAGCCACAGCCCUGGUCUUCCUGUCCUUCUGCGUCAUCUUCGUUGUAGUGAGGUCCUGCAGGAAGAAAUCGGCAAGGCCAGCAGCGGGCGUGGGAGAUACGGGCAUAGAGGAUGCAAACGCUGUCAGGGGUUCAGCCUCUCAGGGGCCCCUGACUGAACCUUGGGCAGAAGACAGUCCCCCAGACCAGCCUCCCCCAGCUUCUGCCCGCUCCUCAGUGGGGGAAGGAGAGCUCCAGUAUGCAUCCCUCAGCUUCCAGAUGGUGAAGCCUUGGGACUCGCGGGGACAGGAGGCCACUGACACCGAGUACUCGGAGAUCAAGAUCCACAGAUGAGAAACUGCAGAGACUCACCCUGAUUGAGGGAUCACAGCCCCUCCAGGCAAGGGAGAAGUCAGAGGCUGAUUCUUGUAGAAUUAACAGCCCUCAACGUGAUGAGCUAUGAUAACACUAUGAAUUAUGUGCAGAGUGAAAAGCACACAGGCUUUAGAGUCAAAGUAUCUCAAACCUGAAUCCACACUGUGCCCUCCCUUUUAUUUUUUUAACUAAAAGACAGACAAAUUCCUA